CCCCCUUUCUCCCGCCCUCUUGGCUCCCCUUCCUCAUCCCCGCCCUUCUCCCUCUUUCCCUUUCCUUUCCCAGCCCUGGAGGUUGAAGAAGCCAGGCCCGCGCCAUCUUGGGUGAGGGCAGCGGGAAGGGGCGGGGCUUAGGGACACCCACGGCGCCAUACAGACUAAGGGCAAGGAGCUGAGAGCGAGGGGGCUUCUCCGUGGCGACACUAGGCGAUGCUAACGUAAAUGAGAGCAGAUACUAUUUCUUUUUCACAGCCUCGGACUCCUCCGAUUAGGAUGUACAGUUGGACUAGGGAAAAAAAAAGAAAGCGAAGUGCGCCAACUGCAAUACAGAGCUGGAAAAGACCGGCACCAUCUUAUCCACUUAGCACUCCAUGGGCUUCGAAGCCUGUCCGGUGCCAUGUUAAUUACGGGCACUGGGCAGCCAUUUUCCCGCUCCUCAUCAUUCGGUAUCUGUCUUUGGGUCACCCGACUGUGGGCUUUGUGAGAGGAAAGGCGUUUCGAGCUGGCUCCAGUGCCCAGACCCAAGCCCCCCACUGCUCAAUGGACACCCCCAGCCCAGACCCGUUGCCUUCGCCUUUGCCCGGGGAGGAAGAGAAACCUCUGGCCUUAUCUCCUCCUGUUCCCCGGGGCCGCCGAGGCCGUCGUCCUGGGGGAGCCACCUCCUCAAAUCGGACACUCAAGGCCUCCCUCCCUCGCAAGCGGGGCCGCCCCCCCAAGUCAGGGCAGGAGCCCCCACUGGUGCAGGUGCAGGGGGUGACAGCCCCAGUAGGCAGCAGUGGCGGGAGCGACCUCCUCCUGAUCGAUGAUCAGGGUGUGCCCUAUACGGUCUCUGAAGGUUCAGCGGCUGGGCCUGAGGGCUCUGGCCCCAGGAAGGCCCCACACUUCUGCCCGGUGUGCCUGCGGGCCUUCCCCUACCUCUCCGACCUGGAGCGCCACAGCAUCUCGCACUCAGAGCUGAAGCCGCACCAGUGCAAGGUUUGCGGCAAGACCUUCAAGCGCUCCAGCCACCUGCGGCGGCACUGCAACAUCCAUGCCGGCCUGCGGCCCUUCCGCUGCCCGCUGUGCCCCCGCCGCUUCCGCGAGGCGGGCGAGCUGGCGCACCACCACCGCGUGCACUCGGGGGAGCGCCCGUACCAGUGCCCCAUCUGCCGGCUGCGCUUUACAGAGGCCAACACGCUCCGGCGCCAUGCGAAGCGCAAGCACCCGGAGGCCAUGGGGGUACCCCUGUGUGCACCAGAUCCAGGGUCUGAACCGCCGUGGGACGAGGAGGGCAUCCCGGCCACAGCAGGGGCCGAGGAGGAGGAGGAGACAGAGGGGAAAGGGGAGCCGGCCUGACCCACACCCCCGGCCAUCGCUCCCUGGGCCAGGUUUAGAGCAGGGAGUUUGGCUGGUGCUGGGCCUGAGCCAGGGGGCCGGGACACCCUUGUUUCCGGUGGUCUUCCCGUUGUGGGAGCAGGUGGAGGGUGGAGACCUAAACUUUGGGGUCCAGCUGCCUUCAGCCCCCCUCCCCCAGACUAACAGACCCUUGGAGGCAGGGGCUGUGGAAAUAAAUCUCUGCCUGCUGGC